CCCUCCGGCGGUAUCAGGUCGCAUCAUCCUCAGUCCUGGUCAGAGGGAGCCGCUCGGUGCCGUCCUCCCUCUCUGCCUUUGCUUGAUCUUCCGCCUGGAAUGCCAUCUCCGACUCUGCGUUUGCCUGGGGUUUCCGGUCCGCCCCUGCGCCAGGUGCCCUAGGACGCCUGCCCUGGAGCCCUCGCCCUAUCCCUUGCCCUAUUUCUGUGAAACUUUCUAUCUCAGUGUGUCAGGAGCGCCGGAAGCGGUUUCUCCGGAGAACUCCGGUCCAAAGAGGACCAGUGAUGUCUUUGGAACUUUCUGGAACUUCCUGACUCUCGCGGCCCCCUCUGCAGCGCACGGAGCAGAGGGUCUAAAGUGAGUGCGCCUCCUGGAGCCCAGGGGCUACAGUUCCGACCAAGGAUGCCAGGGCAGGCUCUCGCCCUGGAGAGAUCACUGGAAGAGAAGGAGCGCGGACACGAGGCUCUACUGACGAAGCGAUCGCCGCCGCUCGCAGGGGCUUGUAAAUCGUGCCCUCUUUCGUUAAGAGGGAAACUGAGGCCCAGGGCAGACAGUGACUCGGCAAGGGUCACUUAGUUUCAGUGCCUGUGUAAUAGAAGGGUCUGUAUUGUAAAAGAAGUCAAAAGCAGCCUUGAAUAAUCGGAACCCUUUUGCCAGAUCAUCUAAUGUCAAUAUGUUUUCUGGCAUUGCUACUUCAACAUCGUCUUCCAUGUCUGGCACUGGUUUGGAGCACUCAUCUCUAUCAGAUUGUCUUCUGCUAAUUCCUCUGGAAGAAGAAGCAGGAAGGAUAAAAGAUUGCUGGGACAACCAGGAAGCACCUGCUCUCUCCACGUGUAGUAAUGCCAAUAUCUUUCGAAGGAUAAAUGCCAUAUUGGAUAAUUCUCUGGAUUUCAGUAGAGUCUGCACUACACCUAUAAACCGAGGAAUUCAUGAUCAUUUGCCAGACUUCCAGGACUCUGAAGAAACAGUUACAAGCAGGAUGCUUUUCCCAACCUCUGCGCAAGAAUCUUCCCGUGGCCUCCCAGAUGCAAAUGACUUGUGCCUUGGCCUGCAGUCCCUCAGUCUGACAGGCUGGGACCGACCCUGGAGCACCCAGGACUCAGAUUCCUCAGCCCAGAGCAGCACACACUCGGUACUGAGCAUGCUCCAUAACCCACUGGGAAAUGUCCUAGGAAAACCCCCCUUGAGCUUCCUGCCUCUGGAUCCCCUUGGGUCUGACUUGGUGGACAAGUUUCCAGCACCCUCAGUUAGAGGAUCACGCCUGGACACCCGGCCCAUCCUGGACUCUCGAUCUAGCAGCCCCUCUGACUCAGACACCAGUGGCUUCAGCUCUGGAUCAGAUCAUCUCUCAGAUUUGAUUUCAAGCCUUCGCAUUUCUCCACCUCUGCCCUUCCUGUCUCUGUCAGGGGGUGGUCCCAGAGACCCUUUAAAGAUGGGGGUAGGGUCUCGGAUGGACCAAGAGCAAGCUGCUCUUGCUGCAGUCACUCCCUCCCCAACCAGUGCUUCAAAGAGAUGGCCAGGAGCUUCUGUGUGGCCAUCCUGGGACCUCCUCGAAGCUCCCAAAGACCCCUUCAGCAUAGAGAGAGAGGCCAGGCUGCACCGACAAGCUGCAGCUGUGAAUGAAGCCACCUGUACCUGGAGUGGCCAGCUUCCUCCCCGGAACUAUAAGAACCCCAUCUACUCUUGCAAGGUGUUUCUAGGAGGUGUUCCUUGGGAUAUUACAGAAGCUGGAUUAGUUAACACCUUCCGUGUUUUUGGCUCUUUGAGUGUGGAGUGGCCUGGUAAGGAUGGCAAGCAUCCCCGGUGUCCUCCCAAAGGGUAUGUGUAUCUGGUCUUCGAACUAGAGAAGUCUGUCCGAUCCUUGCUUCAGGCUUGCUCUCAUGACCCGCUGAGCCCAGAUGGCCUGAGUGAAUAUUAUUUCAAGAUGUCCAGCCGAAGGAUGCGCUGCAAGGAGGUGCAGGUGAUCCCCUGGGUAUUAGCCGACAGUAACUUUGUCCGGAGCCCAUCUCAGAGGCUUGACCCCAGCAGGACGGUGUUUGUCGGUGCUCUGCAUGGAAUGCUAAAUGCUGAGGCCCUGGCAGCCAUCUUGAACGACCUAUUUGGUGGAGUGGUGUAUGCCGGGAUUGACACAGAUAAGCACAAGUAUCCCAUUGGUUCUGGUCGUGUGACUUUCAAUAACCAACGGAGUUACCUGAAAGCAGUCAGCGCUGCUUUUGUGGAGAUCAAAACCACCAAGUUCACAAAGAAGGUUCAGAUUGACCCCUACCUAGAAGAUUCUCUGUGUCAUAUCUGCAGUUCUCAGCCUGGUCCUUUCUUCUGUCGAGAUCAGGUCUGCUUCAAAUACUUCUGCCGGAGCUGCUGGCACUGGCGGCACAGCAUGGAGGGCCUGCGCCACCACAGCCCCCUGAUGCGGAACCAGAAGAACCGAGAUUCCAGCUAGAGGAGCUGGCCUUGCCCAGUGGCCUGUGGCGCCCAAAGCUGGCAGGUCAGGCAAGCAGCCUGCACCACCCUGCCACUGGCGACCAGGGAGCUGGCUUCCCAAGGACAAGGGAAAAUUGUAGUCACCUUUGCACUUGCUGAAUCUGUCUUUGUUUCUGCACUAAUUAAUGCACAUUGAGUUUUGUCAGGUUUUGUUUUCAGGGGGUGUACCAAGGGCAAGGACCCUCUGGCUUACCCUCCAAGCGACUCUGUAGUUUUCCCAGAUUUUAGUUCCUCAUUUUGCAGAUGAAAAGCGGGGAAAAAAAAAAAAAAAAAAAAAACUACGUGUCCAGAAGGUAUUGAGGUAUUGACACGGAUGCCUACACCUAGGUUUAUUUAUUAAAAGCGCUUUUUUACAUUCCUUGCAAUACUGAUGGUGAUGAUGCGCAGGUCUCAUUGGUUUCAUUCUUGCAGUUGCCAUACAGUGCCUUUCCAUUUAUUUAACCCCCACCUGAACGGCAUAAACUGAGUGUUCAGCUGGUGUUUUUUACUGUAAACAAUAAGGAGACUUUGCUCUUCAUUUAAACCAAAAUCAUAUUUCAUAUUUUACGCUCGAGGGUUUUUACCGGUUCCUUUUUACACUCCUUAAAACAGUUUUUAAGUCGUUUGGAACAAGAUAUUUUUUCUUUCCUGGCAGCUUUUAACAUUAUAGCAAAUUUGUGUCUGGGGGACUGCUGGUCACUGUUUCUCACAGUUGCAAAUCAAGGCAUUUGCAACCAAGAAAAAAAAAAUUUUUUGUUUUAUUUGAAACUGGACCGGAUAAACGGUGUUUGAGCGGCUGCUGUAUAUAGUUUUAAAUGGUUUAUUGCACCUCCUUAAGUUGCACUUAUGUGGGGGGGUGGGGUUGAUAGAAGUUUUUAAUCACAAAGUCACAGGACUUUUUUCUUUUGUAACUGAGCUAAAAAGGGCUGCUUUUCGGUGGGGGCAGAUGAAGGCUCACAGGAGCCCUUUCUCUUAGAGGGGGCAAGUACCCUUCCCUUAUAUCUUUAAUUUGAGGAAUGUAUGAGAUAACAGUUGCAGUUGACUGAAAUGCCACUGGAAUUUGAAAACUUGACUUUUUUUUCUUUCCUUUUUUUUUUUUUUUUUUUUUUUAAAAAGAAACAAAAAACCCACAAAAACUACUUGCCCCUCCUAGGGAAGCUGUGUGCCAAAGAACCAGUGUCAUAACCCCUCCCUCCUGCUGAGCUGACGUUGCAUUGUUGCAUAUCCCAGCUACUCUGUGGGUUUUGUGAAGCUGUGUGUGAAGUCUCUACCUCAUUGUAGUAUAUGCAGGCAAGACUGCACUCUCCUACAGAUGUGUGGAGUAAGCUGUGGUGUAGUUUUUUUGGCACAUAAUAAACACGUUGCAGCAGA